AGGUGCGCCGGUAGGGGACGCGCCGGCACAGCAAAAAUGGCGGCGGCAUUACGGGUGGCGGCGGUCGGGGCAAGGCUCAGCGUUCUGGCGAGCGGUCUCCGCGCCGCGGUCCGCAGCCUUUGCAGCCAGGCCACCUCUGUUAACGAACGCAUCGAAAACAAGCGCCGGACCGCGCUGCUGGGAGGGGGCCAACGCCGUAUUGACGCGCAGCACAAGCGAGGAAAGCUAACAGCCAGGGAGAGGAUCAGUCUCUUGCUGGACCCUGGCAGCUUUGUUGAGAGCGACAUGUUUGUGGAACACAGAUGUGCAGAUUUUGGAAUGGCUGCUGAUAAGAAUAAGUUUCCUGGAGACAGCGUGGUCACUGGACGAGGCCGAAUCAAUGGAAGAUUGGUUUAUGUCUUCAGUCAGCAAAUAAUAGGCUGGGCACAGUGGCUCCCGCUUGUCAUCUCAGCACUUUGGGAGGCCGAGGAUUUUACAGUUUUUGGAGGCAGUCUGUCAGGAGCACAUGCCCAAAAGAUCUGCAAAAUCAUGGACCAGGCCAUAACGGUGGGGGCUCCAGUGAUUGGGCUGAAUGACUCUGGGGGAGCACGGAUCCAAGAAGGAGUGGAGUCUUUGGCUGGCUAUGCAGACAUCUUUCUGAGGAAUGUUACGGCAUCCGGAGUCAUCCCUCAGAUUUCUCUGAUCAUGGGCCCAUGUGCUGGUGGGGCCGUCUACUCCCCAGCCCUAACAGACUUCACGUUCAUGGUAAAGGACACCUCCUACCUGUUCAUCACUGGCCCUGAUGUUGUGAAGUCUGUCACCAAUGAGGAUGUUACCCAGGAGGAGCUCGGUGGUGCCAAGACCCACACCACCAUGUCAGGUGUGGCCCACAGAGCUUUUGAAAAUGAUGUUGAUGCCUUGUGUAAUCUCCGGGAUUUCUUCAACUACCUGCCCCUGAGCAGUCAGGACCCGGCUCCCGUCCGUGAGUGCCACGAUCCCAGUGACCGUCUGGUUCCUGAGCUUGACACAAUUGUCCCUUUGGAAUCAACCAAAGCCUACAACAUGGUGGACAUCAUACACUCUGUUGUUGAUGAGCGUGAAUUUUUUGAGAUCAUGCCCAAUUAUGCCAAGAACAUCAUUGUUGGUUUUGCAAGAAUGAAUGGGAGGACUGUUGGAAUUGUUGGCAACCAACCUAAGGUGGCCUCAGGAUGCUUGGAUAUUAAUUCAUCUGUGAAAGGGGCUCGUUUUGUCAGAUUCUGUGAUGCAUUCAAUAUUCCACUCAUCACUUUUGUUGAUGUCCCUGGCUUUCUACCUGGCACAGCACAGGAAUACGGGGGCAUCAUCCGGCAUGGUGCCAAGCUUCUCUACGCAUUUGCUGAGGCAACUGUACCCAAAGUCACAGUCAUCACCAGGAAGGCCUAUGGAGGUGCCUAUGAUGUCAUGAGCUCUAAGCACCUUUGUGGUGAUACCAACUAUGCCUGGCCCACCGCAGAGAUUGCAGUCAUGGGAGCAAAGGGCGCUGUGGAGAUCAUCUUCAAAGGGCAUGAGAAUGUGGAAGCUGCUCAGGCAGAGUACAUCGAGAAGUUUGCCAACCCUUUCCCUGCAGCAGUGCGAGGGUUUGUGGAUGACAUCAUCCAACCUUCUUCCACACGUGCCCGAAUCUGCUGUGACCUGGAUGUCUUGGCCAGCAAGAAGGUACAACGUCCUUGGAGAAAACAUGCAAAUAUUCCAUUGUAAACAAAUCAAAGGAAAAGAAACCAAGAACUGAAUUACUGUCUGCCCAUUCACAUCCCAUUCCUGCCUUUUGCAAUCAUGAAACCUGGGAAUCCAAAUAGUUGGAUAACUUAGAAUAACUAAGUUUAUUAAAUUCUAGAAAGAUC